GUUUAUGCUGCAUUAGGGUUCACUGAACUCUUUAGAUCAUAGGUUUAUUGAUUUCAUGAAACUUGGAGACAGUGUGGUCCUUAUUCUGAAAUUAUUUUUGUCCCCCUUCUCUCCUACAUUCUGAGACGUUAAUGGCGUGUAUGUUAGAUUGCCUGAUACUGUGCUGACUGCAGAAGUCACUUUGGCUUGUUUAUUAUGUUUUGUUUUACAAAUUAUUUGUUUUUCAGCUUGGAUAGUUAAUAUCGUAUGUUUUAAAGCCCUGACUUUUUUUUUUUUUUUUUUUUUUUUUUGGGUAGGUACUUAAUCUGCUGUUAAACCCACAGCGAAUUUUUCAUUUUAUAUUUUGCAUAUUUGAGCUGUGGAAAUUUUACUUAGUUAAAAAAAUCCCCCAUUUCUGUCCUUAUGUUUGUGUUUUUCUUUAAAUUCUUGACCAUAUUUAUAAUAGCUGCUUUAAUUGGCUUGUCUGUUAAUUUCAUCAUUACUUUCAUUUCUGGGUCUGUUUCUGUUAAGUGACUUUUCUUACAGUCAUGAGUCCCAUUUUUCUACUUUUUGAAUGUCUGGUAUUUUUUAUUGGUUGCUGGACAUUGUGAGUGUUGUUGAAAGUCUGGAUUUUAUUUCCUUCCUUUAAAGAGUUGAAUUUUGUAUUGGCUGGUAGUUAAGUUACUGGCAGUUAAUAAGAUCAGCCUAUUAUUAUUAGCAUACUUUUUUUCUGAGGCUUGAUUAUUAGCUUGGGUUAGAAUAGACUUUAUGCUAGCACUGGUUUCCUCCUUAUGAGGUAUGGUCAUUUUAUGGGCAUUAUUCAGUGCCCAAGGUGUUUAACAGUGUUUUUUCUCUCUGGCUGUUCAGAACUUGACUGCCUCCCAGCUUUAGGUGAACUCUUGGAGUGAUAGCUCCCAGUAGUUCUCUGCCUGACCUUGUUGAAUUUUACUGUUUGAAUGUGCAGCCUAGUACUUAGGAACAGUUUCAAAAGAGCCUCUAUCAGAUCUUUGGAGCUUUUUUCCUGAAUAUUCUUUCUGGUGAUCUGUCUCCACAAAUUCCAGCUGUCUUGGCCUUUGUAGGGCCCACCUCAUUUGUAUGCCUUCUCUCAGGGAGUCUAGCUCUGUACUCCCUGUUGUCUAGUGUCUGAAAACAGUAAUUUUAUAUAUUCUGUCCAGUUUUCUGGUUGUUUAUAGUUGGAGAACAAUUUGGUGCUUAUUUAUAUUUUAAAUGUCACAUUUGUCUGUGUAUGUUAUCCUAGCUCAGGUAUCAGCAGACUUUUUCUUAUAGAACCAGAGUAAUUGUUUCAGGCUCUGGGCCAUGUGGCCCCACUUGCAACUCUGUGGUUGUAGUUUGAAAGCAGCCACAGACAAUAUGCAAAUAAAUGGGACAGUUGUGUACUGAUAAAACUUUAUUUACAAAAACAGGUGGUUAGCCCCCAGACCACAGUUUGCUAGCCCUUGAGUUAGUUGACUGAAAUAGAAAUGAUAUUAGAAUUAUGAAAUCUUAUUGUUGGAUGGAAUCCUUGAGACUCUUAUUUCAGGUGUGAAAGGAACCCUUUAAGUCAUAUUGUUCAAUUAGCCCUUUGAUAUUUGAAGCCACUCUACAGUGUCCUAAUCUAGUAUUGACCAGCUUCUCCUUAACCCCCCAUAUCUAUGAUUAACUCUCAGUCAGGGAUUUAUUUCUAGAGGGAGCUCUCACUGUUGUUGUUGCUUUAAUCAUCAGUUUUUCCAUUUGGUUCUGUUGAUACCACUUGGGACUGUGCUGAGCAAAUGUAAUUAAUCUUCUACAUAUCAGCCUUCCAUAUAACAGAAGACUAAAUAACUUCAGAAUCAUUUUAACUAUGUAUUAAGUUCAUUCAGCUGUGUUAUUUUUAUCACAUGGCUUUAUUCUUCUAUUUUAUUCUUGUUGCCGUGUUAAUUUGCUUGAAAGGAUUGAAUGUGCGGCUAGAUAGCCUCUAGCCAUAUGACAUGUUUAGAUUUCCUCACCAGCCUAGUCUUUCAUCUCUUUAUUUGUUGCAUUUUACCUAUAUUCUUAAAGUAUGGAGCUAGGAGCUGAAAGCAGUACUGAAUAAUGACUGAUAAUUUAGAUCUGUUGAAUAGGAUCAAGAUUUCUUACCUUUAUUAAUGUAGCUUAAGAUGGCAGCUACUUUUAAAUAUCUACUUCACAUUGUUUAAUUGUAGUAAACUUAUUGUCAAAUAAAACCUCUGAGCCCUUAUACUUACGCUAUAAACCAACUUUUAAAAAAUCUUUAUACUUUUUAGUUAAUGUUGGUAAACUGAGCAGUGAAAAGAAAAUGACACUUGAGGAAAACAUUUAUGAAUCAGCACAUAUGCAUAUGUGUGUGUAUAUAUAUAUACGUUAGCAUCUUUUAUAUAUGACCUCAUUGUAUGGAGGAAUACCACAUUGUAUUUCUCAUAACAUGGAAAUAACCAGUCAGAUGGGAGGCCCAGUGUCUCGUCAGCAGCCCAUCUACACAGGGAAUCCUUGGCCAGCAACAUAGCUAUGGCUGAGAAGAAUUUGAGCAGAGCCAGAUGGGAUGGAGCAUGCAGCUAGAAAGAUGUCUCUGUCCAGCUGGGUUUUAAUAGUCUAAAAUGGAGAAAAGAAACAGUCAACAACAACACGUUAUUUUAACACAUGGUUAAAUAACCUUUUGGCUUUUGCAGCACAAUUUAUGGGAUAUUGUUCUUCAGUUUAGGAAUUUGUCUAGAAUAAGUCUAUAAAGUAGUAUAAGUGAGUUCUCAAUAUUAGUAGCUUUACAUUCUAUUACCCCAUUUUGAUUAAUUUUGUUUAAAUUUCCUUUUUUUUUUUAAAGCAGAGCUAUAUACUCUUACAGAAUUCAAUUAAAGAAUCAGAUAGGUCUACAAGGUUUAUAAGAACAGUAUUCUGCUCCUGCCCCUAUUUUACCUUCUUUAGAAGCAAACACUCACCCUCUUUUGUUGAUUAUCUUGGUUCUUACUUAAAUGUUUCUAAAUACUGAGGUCAUAGUUACUUUUAGAUUUUUCAAUUCUAUAUCUUCCACUAUCGAAGAGGAGGGUUUAACUCAUUCUUUCUGCCUCCUACAAAGCAGAUGCCCUUUUAAAAAUUUCCUCUCUCCCUCCCUCCCUUCCUUCCCUCCCCUCCUCUCCCCACUCCCCUCUUCUUCCCGCCUCCCCACCUCCCCACCUCCCUCCCCUCCUCUCCCCACCUCCCCACCUCCCUCCUCUCCCUCCCCUCCACACCUCGCUCCCUUCCCCUCCCCACCUCCCUCCCCUCCCCUCCUGUCCCUCCCUUCCCCACCUCCCUCCCCAGCCCGCCACCACCUCUAACUCCUUAGCUCAGGUGAUCCUUCUGCUUGAGCCUCCUGAGUAGCUGGGACUACAUAUGUGUGCCACAAUGCUUCAGCUGUGUCUGUCAGUCUGUAUAUAGAGACAAGGUCUUGCUGUCUUGCCCAGGCUGGUCUCAAAUAGGUCAAGUCGUCCUUCUGCCUUGGCCUCCUAAAGUGCUGGCAUUACAGACAUGAGCCACAGGGCCCAGCCUGCUUACUUUUCUAAAACUUAACUCAUCCCCACAGUUUUUGCCUAUUGUAUGAAACCCCUUUAAGACUCUCAGAUGUAUCAGGUGUUUUAUUAGUUUCACCUUCCUGAAGAAGUCUUUACGGACCUGUCAUAAUCUGGAUUGGUUGCCCUCUGCGCUGGUGUAUAGUUGGCAUCCUGGAGUCAUCAUUCGUUAUGAUUUUAGGGAUUUAUUUUAUUCCCUCUCAGGUCUGUUUCCUGAAUCUUCAGACUUCUUGGUGUAUUCCCUCCUUUUGGCUGAACUCACGGGAAUCAAAUGGCGUAGGUACAAUUUUGGAGGGCAUGGGGACUGUGGACCCAUAAUUUCAGCCCCAGCCCAAGAUGAUCCAAUUCUGUUAAGUUUCAUCCGCUGUCUGCAAGCUAACCUGCUUUGUGUAUGGCGUCGUGAUGUCAAACCAGAUUGCAAAGAGUUAUGGAUAUUCUGGUGGGGAGAUGAACCCAACCUAGUGGGUGUAAUACAUCAUGAACUGCAGGUUGUGGAAGAAGGACUCUGGGAAAAUGGCCUUUCCUAUGAAUGUAGGACGCUGCUCUUCAAAGCGAUCCACAAUCUGUUAGAAAGGUGCCUAAUGGAUAAGAACUUCGUUAGGAUUGGGAAAUGGUUUGUCCGACCCUACGAAAAGGAUGAAAAGCCAGUCAACAAAAGUGAGCAUUUGUCCUGUGCUUUCACAUUCUUUCUGCAUGGAGAAAGUAAUGUAUGCACAAGUGUGGAGAUUGCCCAGCACCAGCCAAUUUAUUUGAUCAAUGAGGAGCAUAUACACAUGGCUCAGUCUUCACCUGCACCAUUUCAAGUACUGGUAAGUCCUUAUGGCUUAAAUGGGACGCUAACAGGCCAAGCAUACAAGAUGUCAGACCCAGCCACUCGUAAGUUGAUUGAGGAAUGGCAGUAUUUCUACCCGAUGGUGCUAAAAAAGAAAGAAGAAUCGAAAGAGGAAGACGAGUUGGGAUAUGAUGAUGAUUUCCCUGUGGCAGUUGAAGUAAUUGUUGGUGGUGUUCGGAUGGUUUACCCUUCAGCAUUUGUUUUGAUCUCUCAGAAUGACAUCCCGGUUCCUCAGAGUGUUGCCAGUGCUGGAGGCCACAUUGCAGUUGGGCAGCAAGGGCUUGGUAGUGUGAAGGACCCAAGUAACUGUGGGAUGCCUCUGACCCCUCCCACCUCUCCAGAACAGGCUAUCCUAGGUGAGAGUGGAGGUAUGCAGAGUGCUGCCAGUCACCUGGUUUCCCAAGAUGGAGGGAUGAUAACGAUGCACAGUCCAAAGAGAUCGGGGAAGAUUCCUCCAAAACUCCACAAUCAUAUGGUCCAUCGAGUCUGGAAGGAAUGCAUCCUCAACAGAACCCAGUCCAAGAGGAGCCAAAUGUCAACUCCAACUCUUGAAGAAGAGCCUGCUAGCAAUCCUGCUACUUGGGAUUUUGUGGAUCCAACCCAAAGAGUCAGCUGUUCUUGUUCCAGGCAUAAGCUUUUAAAACGUUGUGCAGUCGGGCCCAAUCGACCUCCCACAGUAUCUCAACCAGGGUUCAGUGCAGGACCAUCAUCAUCUUCAUCUUUACCACCUCCUGCUUCUUCUAAGCACAAAACAGCAGAAAGACAGGAAAAAGGAGACAAGCUGCAAAAGAGACCCUUAAUACCAUUUCACCAUAGGCCCUCUGUGGCCGAAGAAUUAUGCAUGGAGCAAGAUACACCAGGACAGAAACUAGGGUUGGCAGGGAUAGACUCCUCCUUAGAGGUGUCUAGCAGUAGGAAAUAUGAUAAGCAAAUGGCCGUGCCUUCCAGAAAUACAAGCAAGCAAAUGAAUCUGAAUCCUAUGGAUUCACCUCAUUCCCCUAUAUCCCCUCUGCCACCAACACUCAGCCCUCAGCCACGAGGUCAGGAAACAGAGAGUUUGGACCCACCAUCGGUCCCUGUGAAUCCAGCCCUUUAUGGAAAUGGACUAGAACUCCAGCAGUUGUCUACUCUGGAUGACAGAACUGUCCUCGUAGGCCAAAGACUGCCUCUCAUGGCAGAGGUCAGCGAGACAGCCUUAUAUUGUGGGAUUAGGCCCUCGAACCCGGAGUCAUCAGAAAAGUGGUGGCAUAGUUAUCGUCUCCCACCCAGUGAUGAUGCUGAGUUCAGGCCUCCAGAGCUCCAGGGUGAGAGAUGUGAUGCCAAAAUGGAGGUAAACUCAGAGAGCACUGCAUUGCAAAGACUCUUAGCACAACCUAACAAACGGUUUAAAAUCUGGCAAGACAAACAGCCCCAGUUGCAGCCACUCCACUUCCUUGACCCAUUGCCUCUAUCACAACAACCUGGAGACAGUUUGGGAGAAGUGAAUGACCCAUAUACCUUUGAAGAUGGUGACAUAAAAUACAUCUUUACAGCCAACAAGAAAUGCAAACAAGGGACGGAGAAAGAUUCCCUGAAAAAGAAUAAGUCAGAGGAUGGAUUUGGUACCAAGGAUGUCACUACACCAGGUCAUUCCACGCCGGUGCCUGAUGGGAAAAAUGCCAUGUCUAUUUUCAGUUCUGCUACUAAAACAGAUGUCCGGCAGGAUAAUGCUGCUGGCAGAGCUGGCUCCAGUAGCCUUACACAGGUAACAGAUUUGGCACCUUCCCUGCAUGACUUAGACAACAUCUUUGAUAAUUCUGAUGACGACGAACUUGGGGCUGUAUCACCUGCUCUGCGCUCAUCAAAAAUGCCUGCAGUUGGGACAGAAGACCGACCUCUUGGGAAGGAUGGAAGAGCUGCUGUUCCUUAUCCACCAACAGUUGCAGACUUGCAAAGGAUGUUUCCCACUCCACCAUCUUUGGAACAGCAUCCUGCAUUUUCUCCUGUGAUGAAUUAUAAAGAUGGGAUCAGCUCAGAGACAGUGACAGCAUUAGGCAUGAUGGAGAGCCCUAUGGUCAGUAUGGUUUCAACACAACUCACAGAAUUCAAAAUGGAAGUGGAAGAUGGAUUAGGAAGUCCCAAGCCCGAGGAAAUUAAGGACUUUUCAUAUGUGCACAAAGUUCCAUCCUUUCAACCUUUUGUGGGAUCCUCCAUGUUUGCUCCACUGAAGAUGUUGCCGAGCCAUUGUUUGCUACCUCUGAAGAUACCUGAUGCCUGUCUGUUUCGGCCUUCAUGGGCAAUUCCUCCUAAAAUUGAACAACUGCCCAUGCCCCCUGCAGCCACUUUCAUUAGAGAUGGCUACAAUAACGUGCCUAGUGUUGGGAGCCUAGCAGAUCCAGACUAUCUGAACACACCACAGAUGAACACACCCGUGACGUUGAACAGCGCUGCCCCAGCCAGCAAUAGUGGGGCAGGAGUCCUACCAUCUCCAGCAACCCCUCGCUUCUCUGUCCCCACACCACGAACCCCCAGGACCCCAAGAACUCCCAGAGGUGGGGGCACUGCCAGUGGUCAAGGGUCUGUUAAGUAUGAUAGCACCGAUCAAGGAUCACCAGCCUCCACCCCCUCUACUACACGGCCCCUCAACUCUGUGGAGCCCGCCACCAUGCAGCCAAUUCCCGAAGCCCACAGCCUCUAUGUUACCCUGAUUCUCUCCGAUUCCGUGAUGAAUAUCUUUAAAGACAGAAACUUUGACAGCUGUUGCAUCUGUGCCUGCAACAUGAACAUCAAAGGGGCGGAUGUCGGGCUUUACAUCCCCGAUUCUUCCAAUGAGGACCAGUACCGCUGUACCUGUGGGUUUAGUGCGAUUAUGAACCGCAAACUUGGCUACAAUUCAGGACUCUUCCUUGAAGAUGAGUUGGAUAUUUUUGGGAAGAAUUCUGAUAUUGGUCAGGCUGCAGAGAGGCGCUUAAUGAUGUGUCAGUCCACCUUCCUUCCUCAGGUGGAAGGAACCAAAAAACCCCAGGAGCCACCCAUAAGCCUUCUCCUCCUCCUCCAGAAUCAACACACACAACCUUUUGCUUCACUGAAUUUCCUGGACUACAUUUCCUCUAACAAUCGCCAAACUCUUCCCUGUGUAAGCUGGAGUUAUGACCGGGUGCAAGCAGAUAAUAAUGAUUACUGGACGGAAUGCUUUAAUGCGUUGGAGCAGGGGCGGCAGUAUGUGGAUAACCCCACUGGUGGAAAAGUGGACGAAGCUCUGGUGAGAAGUGCCACUGUGCACUCUUGGCCUCACAGCAAUGUGCUGGACAUCAGCAUGCUCUCCUCCCAGGAUGUGGUUCGUAUGCUGUUGUCCCUGCAGCCCUUUCUCCAAGAUGCCAUCCAAAAGAAGCGCACGGGCAGGACCUGGGAGAACAUCCAGCAUGUGCAGGGACCACUCACUUGGCAGCAGUUCCAUAAAAUGGCAGGACGGGGAACCUACGGUUCGGAAGAAUCUCCUGAGCCGUUGCCCAUCCCCACUCUGCUGGUAGGCUAUGACAAGGAUUUCCUCACCAUCUCGCCAUUCUCCUUGCCGUUUUGGGAGAGGCUCUUGUUGGACCCAUAUGGGGGCCACCGUGAUGUUGCCUAUAUUGUGGUGUGUCCAGAAAAUGAGGCCUUGCUCGAAGGAGCCAAAACUUUCUUCAGGGACUUGAGUGCUGUAUACGAGAUGUGUAGGCUUGGGCAGCACAAGCCCAUCUGCAAAGUGCUACGUGACGGGAUCAUGCGCGUGGGAAAAACUGUGGCACAGAAGCUGACAGAUGAGCUUGUGAGUGAGUGGUUUAACCAGCCUUGGAGCGGCGAGGAGAAUGACAAUCAUUCCAGACUCAAACUUUAUGCGCAAGUUUGCCGCCAUCACCUAGCACCUUAUUUAGCCACUCUGCAGCUUGAUAGCAGCCUAUUGAUACCACCUAAAUACCAGACCCCACCAGCAGCAGCACAGGGACAAGCUACGCCAGGGAAUGCUGGGCCCUUAGCUCCAAAUGGAUCAGCAGCUCCCCCAGCUGGCAGUGCAUUUAAUCCCACCUCGAAUAGUAGUUCUACAAAUCCUGCAGCAAGUAGUUCUGCAUCUGGUUCCUCUGUGCCACCGGUCUCAUCGUCUGCCUCUGCUCCUGGUAUUAGCCAGAUAAGCACUACCUCUUCUUCAGGAUUCAGUGGUAGUGUUGGAGGGCAGAACCCCAGCACUGGGGGCAUUUCUGCGGAUAGAACGCAAGGGAACAUAGGCUGUGGUGGAGACACUGACCCUGGGCAGAGCUCUUCUCAGCCCUCACAGGAUGGACAAGAGAGUGUUACAGAAAGGGAGAGAAUAGGAAUUCCCACGGAGCCUGACUCUGCAGACAGCCAUGCCCACCCUCCAGCUGUUGUCAUUUACAUGGUGGACCCGUUCACGUAUGCUGCAGAGGAGGACUCCACUUCUGGGAACUUUUGGCUGUUGAGCUUGAUGCGCUGCUACACAGAAAUGCUGGAUAAUUUACCUGAGCAUAUGAGAAAUUCUUUCAUUCUCCAGAUUGUGCCUUGCCAGUACAUGCUGCAGACAAUGAAGGAUGAGCAAGUUUUCUACAUUCAAUACUUGAAGUCCAUGGCAUUUUCAGUGUACUGCCAGUGCAGGCGACCACUGCCUACACAGAUCCACAUUAAAUCCCUCACGGGAUUUGGGCCUGCAGCCAGCAUUGAGAUGACCCUCAAGAACCCUGAGCGGCCCAGCCCAAUCCAGCUUUACUCCCCUCCCUUUAUAUUGGCCCCAAUCAAAGACAAGCAGACAGAGCUGGGAGAGACGUUUGGUGAGGCGAGCCAGAAAUACAAUGUGCUCUUCGUGGGCUAUUGUCUGUCUCACGACCAGCGCUGGCUUUUGGCUUCCUGCACUGACCUCCAUGGGGAAUUAUUAGAGACCUGCGUUGUAAAUAUUGCUUUACCAAACAGGUCACGGAGGAGUAAAGUAUCUGCACGUAAAAUUGGACUACAGAAGUUAUGGGAGUGGUGCAUAGGGAUUGUCCAAAUGACAUCUCUACCCUGGAGAGUUGUAAUCGGGCGACUUGGGCGUCUUGGCCAUGGGGAGCUUAAAGAUUGGAGUAUCCUCCUUGGAGAAUGUUCACUACAGACAAUCAGCAAAAAGCUCAAGGAUGUGUGCCGGAUGUGUGGAAUCUCUGCCGCAGACUCUCCUUCUAUCCUUAGUGCCUGCCUGGUUGCCAUGGAGCCCCAGGGGUCCUUUGUAGUGAUGCCAGAUGCUGUCACAAUGGGCUCUGUUUUUGGCCGAAGUACUGCACUGAACAUGCAGUCAUCUCAGCUCAACACCCCUCAAGAUGCUUCUUGUACACACAUCUUGGUGUUCCCAACAUCAUCAACCAUCCAGGUGGCUCCAGCCAACUACCCCAAUGAAGAUGGGUUUAGCCCCAACAAUGAUGAUAUGUUUGUUGACCUUCCAUUCCCAGAUGAUAUGGACAAUGAUAUUGGCAUAUUAAUGACUGGGAACCUCCAUUCCUCUCCCAACUCUUCCCCAGUACCCUCCCCAGGCUCUCCUUCUGGAAUUGGUGUGGGCUCUCACUUCCAGCAUAGUCGGAGCCAGGGUGAGCGUCUUCUUUCUAGAGAAGCACCAGAGGAGCUAAAGCAGCAGCCCCUGGCCCUUGGGUAUUUUGUAUCAACUGCCAAAGCUGAGAAUCUUCCCCAGUGGUUUUGGUCAUCGUGUCCCCAGGCUCAAAACCAGUGCCCUCUCUUCUUAAAGGCUUCGCUGCAUCACCACAUUUCAGUAGCACAGACAGACGAACUUCUGCCUGCCAGGAAUUCUCAGCGGGUUCCACACCCUCUUGACUCCAAAACCACGUCGGAUGUUUUAAGGUUUGUUUUGGAGCAGUACAACGCUCUGUCCUGGCUCACGUGCAAUCCGGCCACCCAGGACCGUACUUCCUGCCUUCCCGUCCACUUUGUGGUGCUCACUCAGUUGUACAAUGCCAUCAUGAAUAUACUUUAAUUGGAAAAGCACUUGUUCUCUCUGGCUCAGUUCCUUCUCCCUGCAACCUCAGUCCAAGGAACCUGCUACACUCUGCAAAUAACCCACAUCCUUUUCUUCAGACCACUCUCCACAGUCCUGCACUGUGAUUCCUUCUCAGCAGGCACAUGUCAAUUCUGCAGUGUUCAUUACCAGAGUGACUCCUUGACACUUCUCUCAUGGACCUGGAAACUUCCAUAAGUGGUGACUUUCAGCCAGUGCGGUGGUGUGUGUAGCCCCAACCACUGGUCCCCAGGAAGUGGUGGUGGUUGAUGGCUUUUCAGCGGGAAACAGAAGAGACAGUGUCCUUUUGCACAAGAGUCUGUGUUUUCAGCCUCUGUAUACAAUUGAGGGCAGUCUAGCCCUUUGGAUGAAAUCCUCUUAGUUACUGGUGUAUGGCCUGUGGGUUACCUGAACUCCAUAAUCUGGGACUUUUUAAAAAUAAGAACCAGCUCAAGUACAUGGUUUCAUACUGGGGUUUCUGUCUCCCUAGUGUUCCCAUCCAGAUUAGCAUGAGUGCUUUGGUUGACUUCAAACCUGUGUGUCAAUGCAGAAGGUCUGGAGACAGCUUCAUUUUGUUUAUUUAUUUUAAUUUGUUUUGUCAUAUGGUUUUUGUGACUUUAUUUUUUUAAUUCACAAGGACCAGGUACAGUAGCUGAAACCCAAUUCAGAUCCACCAUAGGAUUCUUUGACUACAUACCUCUGUCCUAGAAGCCGGAAAAGGAGUAAAAACACAUUGGGGAGAUCAUGCCUAAAAGUAAUAUAUUCAAAACCACCCAGCAGUAGGUUUUGUUAACAACAAACUGGAUUUUAAAAGUUCUGCCAUGUUAAGUGGCCAGCAUUUCAUGAAGGAUAACAUUUUUAUACAGAAGGCAGUCAAGCUCAACUCAGAGCCAUGGAGGCAAGUACCUUAAUUAGUUUUAUAUAGUCACAACGGAAAUAUAUUUUCUAGUGAAUUCUUAUUGGAAGCCAGGUCUCUCCUCUCAUUAGAUCAAAAGGGACUUAUGUACAUACAACAAUUGAAAGUGUUUGCUCAUGAAAUCAGUUAUAAAUAUGGUGAAUUUUUUCUGGACCAUAGGAAUAUUAUUUCAAAGAAAUAUUACAACUUAACCAUUAAAUUAGUACUUGAAGUUGAGCCUUUGUGGUGGGACUUUUUAAAAAAAUGCCUUUUUAAAGCAUUAAUGGCUAAUUGAAGUAUUUUAUGACUCCUCAUUCCUGGCCCAGAGGGUUGUCUUUGAAACCCUGUUUCUAACCCUUGUGUUGUGUGUUUCUGUCUGAGGACAGUGGGUGUGUACUGGCCUCCCGGGAGCCACUGUGACCAGGCCUUUGAGCUCUUGUCAUCUGUGGAGAGAAUCAUGCAAAUUUUAAAAGUUCUUCCAAGAGACUUCCAUGUCCUGGUUAUUAACAAAAAAGGAAAAAUGUAAUAAUUGAUAUGAUUUUGUAAAAGUAUUUUUCUUGAAAUAAUCUAAAGUUUAAAACAUUAUAUUAAAAAAAAAGUUGUGUGGUGGGAAUGUGAAAGCAGAGAAAUAACUUGUAAAUGGAUAAUUUUGUUCUCUGUACCACCAGUUGAAGGGGGGGUUGACUUUCGCAAUGUAUAGGAUAAAAAAUCUGAUAUAUCAAACCAUUUGUAUCUAAUGUGUACAGUGUAAAAUUGACUUUAAAAAUAUUGCAGUGCUAUUUUUUCUUAAUCAGAAAGGAAAAUUCUCAAGGCCUUUUGAAGAGCAUAAGAAGAUGAAGAUUGUAAACUUGUAUAAAAUUAUCUUGGUGAGAAGACAAAUUGUAAAGUAGAUAUUUGUAAUCUUUUACCACUUUGGGGUUGCUUUUUUCCCGGAAUUCAUCAGAACUUUGAAUUUUUUUUUUAAAUGGGCUGUUUUUAAUGCAGGGGCUUUUCUUCCCUAGAAACCCAAUUCUAAGCAGAAAAAGAAAAAAAACACAAAAAAUAAAAAACCCCUACAAAAAAACUUUAAAAAAAAUGGCAGCAAAGGGUAGUUUUCAUCUGGUGUCUUUUAUUUAAGUUUUUUAAGUUAAGAAAAGCUGGUGACAUAUUUAUACGUUUUUGUGCAAAAAUAAAUGAAUGGCAAUAGAUUUUAAAAAAUCUUAUUAUGUACUUCUGUGUGAAAAAGUCUGUAUAAUAUUUCCCUUAAAUAUGCAUUAUUUUACUUGUGAGUUUUUUACUGAAUUAAUCUGAAAUGUACAAGCCCUGGAUUUGCUACAGAGUGAGAAGUUAUUUUAUUUUUUUUUAUUUUUAAUUUUGGAAAUUCUGCAGAAAUCAGAACUCUUACCAUGGUUUGAACAAAAAAAGGGGAAAUGGGGAGGGGAAAAGGGUGGGAUUGUCCAGCAUGCUUGUAUGUAUAUUUCAGAACCUUUUUUAAAUGUAAAAGCUGUACAUUUCUGGGAAGUUCUGAAUUUCUUUUGUUUCCUUUUUUCCUUCAAGCAUUUUGCAGUGAGCUUCUUUUAUAUAUAGCAAACAAUUUGAAAGAAUACAAAAAUAUGUGAAGUUCAUUUAAAAAAAUAACUACAGUAUAGCGCUGGUACAGUACACUAAAAGACUUUGAUAAAAAGAAACAAUAAUAAAAGGCCUCCAUUUUAAAUGUCAUUCAUAUAUACCUUGUGGAUGAGAGCUAUAUACUUUUACACACUUUUUUAGAGGAAUAAAUUAUUGAAUUACUGAA